AGGGCGUGCUGCAGUCCCGGCGGCAGCGGCGGCGGCGGCGGCGGCGGCGGCUGGAGGUGCAGCCUCCCAGGUGGGAGGCGGGGGCUGCGGGCGCAGGAAAAGGCGCCUUGGGAGCGGGCGCUCGGCGGGGCCUCCUCGGGCCCCGGGCGCGGCGCGGCGAGUGGGAGCGAGCGCGCCAGGACCACGCAGGCGCCCUGCUCCGGCUGGCCCUCGGCCGGCGCGCGGCGCGGGAGCAGCCCGCAGCCCGCCUCCCGCGCCCCCGGCAGCCCCCUGGCAGCCCGCAGCCGCCCGUCCGGAGCAGCCCCUCGGCAGCCCGCGCAGGCCGCCGGCCCGGGAGAGCGCGCGGCGGCGGCGGCGGCGGGACGGCCCCGAGCGCGCCCUCCCGCCUGCGGCCACUCGCAGCCGGCGCUGGCCGGGCCGGCGCGCCCCGCAGGCGGCUAGAGCGCGGCCUCGGCCUCGGCGCGGGCUUGCCCCGGGCCGUAGCCCGCGAGAGGCGGCGCGGGCGGCCGAGGGCACUGACGGCGUCGCGGGACGCUCCCGGGCGGCGGCGCAGCGGCAGCGGCAGCGGCAGCGGCAGCGCAGGGGGCGGAGGCAGGGGGCGCCCCCAGCCAGGAUGCUGCGGUUCCUGCGCCGGACCUUUGGCCGCCGCUCCAUGCAGCGCUACGCGCGGGGCGCGGCGGGGCGCGGGGCCGCCGGGCUGGGGGACGAGCGCGAUGGGGGGCCACGGGGGGGCCCGGCCGCCGCCGCCUCCUCCUCGGCGCUGCCCGCCGCGCCCGGGGGCAGCGUGUUCCCGGCGGGCGGCGGGCCCCUGCUCACCGGCGGCGCGGCCGUGCACAUCUCCGCCGCCGGCGCCGCCAAGGCCACCCUCUACUGCCGCGUCUUCCUGCUCGACGGGACCGAAGUGAGCGUGGACCUGCCGAAACAUGCCAAAGGCCAGGAUUUGUUUGAUCAGAUUGUGUACCACUUGGACCUUGUGGAAACAGAUUACUUUGGCCUCCAGUUCCUCGACUCUGCCCAGGUUGCGCACUGGCUGGAUCAUGCCAAACCCAUAAAAAAGCAGAUGAAAAUUGGACCUGCUUAUGCUUUACACUUUCGAGUUAAAUACUAUUCUUCAGAACCAAACAACCUUCGUGAGGAGUUUACAAGGUACCUGUUUGUUUUACAACUCAGGCAUGACAUUCUUUCUGGAAAAUUGAAAUGCCCUUAUGAAACAGCUGUGGAAUUAGCUGCUCUCUGUCUACAAGCGGAGCUUGGGGAGUGCGAGCUUCCAGAACACACACCAGAGCUUGUGUCUGAGUUUCGGUUCAUUCCAAAUCAGACAGAAGCAAUGGAAUUUGAUAUCUUCCAGAGAUGGAAAGAGUGCAGGGGAAAGAGCCCUGCCCAGGCGGAACUCUCCUAUCUGAAUAAAGCGAAGUGGCUGGAAAUGUAUGGGGUAGACAUGCACGUUGUCAGGGGAAGAGAUGGCUGUGAAUAUUCUCUUGGACUGACCCCGACAGGCAUAUUAAUCUUUGAAGGAGCUAACAAAAUAGGCUUAUUCUUUUGGCCUAAAAUUACCAAAAUGGAUUUUAAAAAGAGCAAAUUGACACUCGUGGUGGUCGAGGAUGAUGAUCAGGGACGUGAGCAAGAGCACACGUUUGUGUUCCGGUUAGACAGUGCCAGGACCUGCAAACACCUUUGGAAGUGUGCAGUUGAGCACCACGCAUUCUUCCGACUGCGGACGCCAGGAAACAGCAAAUCCAAUAGAUCCGACUUUAUCAGGCUGGGCUCUCGCUUCAGAUUCAGUGGGCGGACAGAAUAUCAAGCUACACAUGGCUCCAGGUUACGAAGAACCAGCACCUUUGAGAGGAAGCCUAGUAAACGUUAUCCAUCCCGGAGACAUUCAACGUUCAAAGCAAGCAACCCAGUGAUAGCAGCCCAGCUCUGCUCUAAAACAAAUCCAGAAGUCCAUAAUUACCAGCCUCAAUAUCAUCCUAAUAUCCAUCCCAGCCAGCCCCGGUGGCAUCCUCACUCUCCAAAUGUCAGCUACCCGCUCCCUUCCCCAGUGCUUAGCAGCUCGGACCGGUUGCCUUUUGGCAUUGAGGAGAAUGGGGGCACACCGUUCCUCACCGCAGCUUCAGGAAGGCAUCACCACCAGCACCAGCAUCAGCAUCAGCACCAGCACCACUCAAACUACAGCCUCUCACUGACCCUGGAGAACAAAGAGGGGCCUCUGAGGUCCCCAAACUCCAGCAGCAAGUCCCUUACAAAACUGAGUCCAGGAACACCUGCCUUGUUCAGUGAAGCCGCUGCCCAUCUAAAGAAGCUGGAACUGGAAACUGUGAAGGCUGCUGGACCCUGGCCUCCUCUGCACAUCAACAUAAACAAGGCUGAAGAAAAGAAAGUCUCGGAGAAAACUCUUCAGACUCCACUUUUGCCUUCCCCUGUUGCGGAUCAUGUGAAGUGUAACAUUCUGAAAGCCCAGUUGGAAAAUGCUUCCCGAGUGAACAUCCAGGGUGGAAAGGAGGAAUCACCGUUUGUAAAUAUCAAUAAGAAAUCCAGUCUUCAGGACGCUAGUGUAAGAAGUCCUAUUCCUAUUCGUGUGGAAACUGCCCAGCCAGCUGUGGAAAAGCCGGAAAUCAAGCCUCCCCGAGUGAGGAAGUUAACAAGACAGUAUAGUUUUAACCGCAGUGAUGAAGACGACCUCCCUCCAGACCUGGCCGAGGCAGUGGGAGUGACCACAUCUACAACCACAAACACCACAACGGCCGCCACACAAGUCUCCGUGCCGCUGCCGUCCCCCAAGGUCCAGAAUGUCAGCUCGCCUCACAAGUCAGAAGGCAAAGGCCUGCUGUCCCCUGGGGCCAAGAGCCCCUCUGACCGAGGAGGUGCCUUUACCCUGGAGCCGGGUGAUCUUCUGAUGGAUUUCACAGAAGCCACUCCUCUGCACUGGCUCAAGGCCACACCCCAGCUUUCCAGGCCCCUCGCACCUCCUGCCAUCUUCCAUCCUCUGCAUACAGGUCUCCCCUUAGGGAUGGCAGCCCUUGUGGGACUCCUGCAGGCAGAGCCCGCCAGCAACCCCCACUGUGCCCACUCUCGCUGUUCUCCUCCACUCUCUCUCCCCAUGAAGGAAGAGACCACUGGAGUUUGCAUGUACCCUCCAAUCAAAACGAGGCUGAUAAAAACAUUCCCGGUUGAUACAAUGAACCCGUUUCCUGAUACUUUCACCACAGGGCCACAGUUUACUGCAGACUUCAGAGACAGUAAAUUACAGUGCUGUCCUGGCCCGACUUCCCCGCUGAUCCCAGCAGCGACCCUGAGGCCUUUGACAGAGACCGUCUCCACAGUGCAGACCAUUUACACCACCCGGAAACCUGUUUCUCUGGCAGCCAGUGCAGAGACACUCCGGCAGGAACUGGAGAGAGAGAAGAUGAUGAAAAGACUGUUGAUGACCGAACUGUGAAAUUCUCCCCUUGUCACCUGGAAGAUGGCAUGGUGCCUUCUGUCCGUCUUCUUUCUUCGGGCUUUGUGUGCUCACUCUAGCACAGCAUACAAGUGUGUGCUCUGUUCGCCCAGGUCUCCAUGGUUAGUUGAAGCCAAUUUCUGGCUUGACUUUUAUGGGAAAAGUUAUUUUAUGUCUCCUAAGCAUUAGAGUUUUUCUAUUACUCUAUGUAGUUGAGACAGGAUUUGAUAAGUCUAGGAAAAGAAAGAUGGGAAAACGGGAUUCCUUUUCAGAAGUACCUGUGUGUAUCUGUUAAUAACCACAGGGGUUAAUAUGAUGUAGGAUCUUUUACUAUCAAUUUCAACCAUUUGAUUUUGUAUGAUUGAAACUUGCACCGAGCUUUGACUGUUUGUUAAAGAGUCAUUUUUAAUGAAAGAAUAAUUCUUUAUUGCUGGUUUUUCAUUUACACUGAUAAAUACACAGAUCUUAUAAAGUCUUUAACAUUCAUUUGUAUUCAGAUGUGAGUAGAAGAACUAAAAAAAGAAAGUUACAUAUCACUAUGACUGAAGGUACUUCAGCUUAAUCUGAAAUAUAAUUUAACUUGUGAACUCCUUGGAUAUGAUAUUAUUUGGAAUAAACAGAAUUUAUCAUUGAACCCAAAGUAGGAAAUGAUAGCUUACAUUGUCUAAAAAUCCUUACAAGGUUAAGAUGAUUCAAUAUCAAGAAGAUUCAGAAAAUUAUUUCUAAAGUUGAUCGAUUCAUGUCGUAUUGAUAGAAUCUUGACCAGAAGAAAUUUUGCUCUUUUUAUAUAGUUUCAAGAAAUGUGUUUUUAAAUUUUUAUUAAUGCACUUGAACAACUUUGCAGGAAUAAAGCAACCCCCUAACCACAAAAUAUCCCUCUAAAUUAGUUCCCUAGCUUUCUCAAUGAAUACACACAUAUUUUUACAUAGCUAUGAUCGUUGUGUACAUUCUCCUUUGUUUUACUUCUCGGCCUAACACUUGUCUCCUCUUGUCAACACAGAUUCUACUCUCACCAAUUUAAAUGUCUUUAUAUCCAUGUAACAUGGGUAACCUCACUUCACCCCAUUAUUAGAUAUUUGAGUUAUAUCUAAUUUUUCACUCUUAUAAAUAGUGCUGCUAUGAAUGUCUGUAAAAAAAAAAAACUGCUCCUUCUUUUGGAUUAUUCCCUUAGGAAUAUCUCCAAAGAGGGAUUACAAGGUCAAAGAGCAUGAAGUAUUUUAUAGCUCUUGUUUUAUAUUGCCAGAUUGCUUUCUAGAAAGAUCCAAUCUUUGGGUUGGAAGGACCUUAAAGGUCAUCUAGUUUAGCCUCCCCACCCCCUCUGAAUGCUUGAAUCCCCUCGACAAUUUAUGAUGCCACCAGCAAUGUAUAAGCAUUUCUGUUUACCAAUAGCUCUGCCAGUAUUGGGUUUUGCCAUUUUUAUUUAUUUUUGCUAGUUUAAUAGGUAUGUAUAGUUGUUCUUGAAGAGUUGUUUUAUUUCAUUAAUUGCUAGCAAGGCUGAGCACUUUUCCAUGUGAUGAUUUACUAGUUGUAUUUCCUUGUGUGUAAAAUGUUCAUUCAUUUCUUAUGACCACUUGUUAAGAGGAACUGAUCUCAUAUAUUUGUAUCAGAACUGUAUUUUUAUGUUAUAUUGUAUAGUUUGCUCUCCUGCCCCUCUCCUUAAAACUGAAUGGUGCCAAUAAUUUGAUACUAAUGACUACAAAAAAAGGUAAUGCCUCAUUUACUAGUAUUGUUGUAAAAUGAGGAAUGUAUGUGAAUAUUCAGAUAACCGAGGAUUAACCCUUUAAGUGCUGAAUCUUUAAAAUUUUAAUAUAUUUUUUUUUGAGGGAAAUCUUUCUAAAAUGUAUUACGCACUUCCCUGCCUUAGUAAACAGAGUAUACUGGAGAGUAUUUAACCUUUUCUUGAUGAGUCAUGGUCAUGAUUAUAAACAUCAGCCCCUUUUAUACCUUGGUACGGUGCAGUGAUAUCAUUAAGAGCUAUCAAUAUGUGUAGGGCUUGGCUUGGCCUUUUAUAGGAUAUUAUGCUGUUCUCACUGAUGGUUUUUUACUGCUCUCUGCUCUGUCAGUGGAGCUAUCCGGGGCAAUUGUAGCGUUUGGGUCCUUUUACCCCUAUGUCCCCCGGCUAUACUUUUAAAACAGCUUUAGCUGUUCUUUAUCUUGUGCACAUGAUACAAAAUAUGUUCCCGUACAAUAUGGGGCUGUCACUUCUUGCCAACCCAGCACCCUCUUCCUCUUCUAACCUGCUUUCUGAGGCUUCUGCUCUUCACCUCCUGCUCGCUGAUGGAAACCUCCAGGGCAAAGCUGAAGGUUUCUUGGGGAAGCCAGGAAAGCCAGUAUUUCCUAUGUGUCAGAUCUGCUUGGCUUCCAAGAAGGGAUGCAUGGGCUUUUUGGCCAGUGUUUCCAGGAGGCUCUGGGCUUCCUGCUUCUUCCCCGCUUCCCCCAGAGUUCACAGAUGUUGAAGUUUCUGAAGGUUGACGUCACUGGAAGUCUGACCACAAACAAGUUGGCUGUUACUGUAUUUGAAACCCAGUACCUUUGGCAGCUCACCUCUAACCAGUAAAAUAAGAGGAUUCCAUGGUUUCA